GUAGGAGGAAGGAGACGCCAUUAGAGGGAGGCAGAGAGGGAUCGUUCUUCGCUUUUCCUCCGGUGCCUGACGUGGUGGGCUGGGGCCCUUCAUUCUCGGACUUUCCCUCAGCCCUUCCAGGCCUCGCCCGAGGAGGGCGUGGGGACAGCGCCCGGGUCGGCGGGGCCGGGGCGGUGGGGGCUGAGCCGGCCGUGGCUGUGAAGGCGCUGCCGCGGCUGUCGGGAGGGCGGCGCGACACUCGGGCUCGGGCGGCCGGGAAGCGACGGGAUGGCUGCGGCCGGCGGCGGCGGCGGCGGGGCGGCGGCGGCGGGCCGAGCCUACUCGUUCAAGGUGGUGCUGCUGGGGGAAGGCUGCGUGGGGAAGACGUCGCUGGUGCUGCGCUACUGCGAGAACAAGUUUAACGACAAGCACAUCACCACUCUGCAGGCAUCAUUCUUAACAAAGAAGUUAAAUAUUGGUGGGAAAAGAGUAAACCUUGCCAUAUGGGAUACGGCAGGUCAAGAGAGAUUCCAUGCAUUGGGUCCAAUUUACUACAGAGAUUCAAAUGGAGCGAUUUUAGUUUAUGACAUAACAGAUGAAGAUUCUUUUCAGAAGGUAAAAAACUGGGUCAAAGAAUUACGGAAAAUGUUGGGAAAUGAAAUCUGUUUAUGUAUAGUUGGUAAUAAAAUAGACUUGGAAAAGGAGAGACAUGUUUCCAUUCAAGAAGCAGAGUCGUAUGCAGAAUCUGUGGGAGCAAAACAUUAUCAUACUUCAGCCAAACAGAACAAAGGAAUUGAGGAACUCUUUCUUGACCUUUGUAAAAGGAUGAUAGAAACAGCACAAGUGGAUGAGAGAGCAAAAGGCAAUGGCUCUAGUCAGCCGGGAACUGCAAGGCGAGGUGUACAGAUUAUUGAUGAUGAACCUCAAGCCCAGACCAGUGGUGGAGGGUGCUGUUCUUCUGGAUAACUGUUCACGCCUAAGAAAUUAAAAGACAGAACAAAACUGUGGAUCAUUGCCCUCAACAUGAAGACUGCCAUAUUCCAAGUCACAUUAUUUUACCAAUGGAAUUAUAGAAUUAACAGUAUUUUAAAUUACGUUUAUAACACUGCAGAGACCUUAAGUGCUAAACUUAGUGGAGUUUGUGACCAGAGAAUUGGCAUUUUCUACAAAUGUUUUUUUUUGUUUUUUUUUUGUUUUUUUUUGUUUUUUUUUGAGACGGAGUCUCGCUCUGUCACCCAGGCUGGAGUGCACUGGCUUGAUCUCGGCUCACUGCAAGCUCCACCUCCCAGGUUCACGCCAUUCUCCUGCCUCAGCCUCCCGAGUAGCUGGGACUAUAGGCGCCCACCACGACGCCCGGCUAAUUUUUUGUAUUUUUAGUAGAGACGGGGUUUCACCAGGUUAGCCAGGAUGGUCUCGAUCUCCUGACCUUGUGAUCCGCCCGCCUCGGCCUCCCAAAGUGCUGGGAUUACAGGCGUGAGCCACCGUGCCCGGCCUACAAAUGUUAACAAAGCAAUUACCAAUGGCCUUUUUACAUAUUUUUUCUUUAAUGAGGAAUAAUAUGCAUGUAGAAAAGACCUACUUAAAGUCUUCAUUUAUAUUCUUUCAAAUCAAAUCUUUAUUUAAUAACUUAUAUAUGUUGUUGGAAUGGUUACAUUUUUGCAGCCCUUUGUAUUUUGUGGUAGUUGAAAUUGUAUCACUUCUAAACAGCAAACUGUUUUUGUUUUUAAUUAGCAGAUAUCUGAAGUACUAUUUUUGCAGGGUUUGCACAGGCCCGUAACUGUCUACUACUUUGAUAUAAUCUGUAUACAUCCUGUAUGCUGAGCUGGUAAAAUACAUUGUAAAUUACAUAUUAAAUAUUUUAUCUGCUUUUACAAGCGCAAGGUGCAAAAAUAUAUACAAUAGUCUCAUUGAUGACUGUAAAGUGAAUUAACAUUUGGUGAUUAUGCCUAGCUUUUUUGACUAAUAUAAAGAUCAUAGCUCCCCUUCACUUCUGUCUUAACUUGAACAUGGCGUGUUUAAAUUUUCAUACAUACUUUACUUGAAUUAUUGCUGUUGUCACAUAUUUUUGCCUCUGUGAGUUCAUCUGAUGAUUGAGCAGUAGCAUUUGCCUUUUGGGUUUUUUGUUUGUUAUUAUAGAAGAGAUGACUUCUGCUGAUUUUGCUUUAGAAUGGUUACCUUAGAAGAAUUUGGGUGGCUCAUGUUGAAUUUCACUUCUGCAAUAGCUUUCAUUUUCUCAUAGGCUUUAUAAGAGAUGGGUUCAGUGGUAUGAGCAGAGGAAGAGAUCCCAGAUAGUAGCCAGUUAACCAAGACUCAUUCAUAUAGCACGUAGUUUAUGUUCCUGAGGCAGCACUUUUAGAUCCUUUGUGAGCAAGUUCUAUUUGUUCAUUGCUUGCCAGAGAUGAACACAGAAUGUUCUGUUUCAUUUUACAAGAACUAUCCUGAGUUUCUGUGGAUGGAAACAUUACAUGUAAUGCAGAUAUAGUGAACACUGGAAAGAUUUAUUAAAGAAUUAUAUUUGUGUAUACUUUAUAAAUUAGUCCCUCAUUAGAUUUUUUUUUCUUAAGCAUAAGACUGAACUUAAAUGUGUUAAUUUUAGUAGAAUCAGGCACUGCUCGCAGAAGGAACACAGAUUGUAGAGAUUAACAUAAAUUGUUCUUGUUCUAAUAUAUAUAUUUUUUCAUUUCUGUCGUGCUUGGAAAACUAGUAAAUAUUAUGUCUAAGAUAAAAUGGAAUGGCCCCUGGAUUUACUUCUUAUAAGAAGCAGUAGUAUGUAAUAAAGCUAUUAGCAUGAGCAAUUAAGAGGCUAUAAAGAGAUUAUAGUUACAAAAGAAAUACUGCCAUAUUUUUAAGUUAAUAACUUAAACCUUCUCAAAUGGGUUAAAAGUUGAAUGAAUUGACACCCUGAUGUUAUGAUGUUGGAAUUUUAACUUAAACUGGGAGGCAUUCUGUGAGCCUUCACUUUACCUUCUUUAAUUAUUGUCCUUGCUAAACUCAACACAGACUUUUCUGUUAUGUGUUUUUGAGGAAGUUGGGGUGGGAAGAGUCAGGGAGAUAAGCUAAAAUUGUCUUCUUUUAUGGGGUAAUUGUACUCUGUAGUCUCUUGGUUUCCUGUGAAGUUAGUAUUUAUGUGGGGGUGGGGGAAGGUAGCAAGAAUCAUGGGUAUCACGGUACUUUGUUUUUGACCUCCUGGCUCUUUCAGACAGAGUGAAGAAAGCUUUUCCAUUCUUACUGUUGUAGAAGUAGAUAGGAAAUAAGCUUUUCUCAUUACAGUGAAAUAUGUUUUAAAAACUAGAGUAGCUGGGCACAGAGGCAUGCAUUUGUAGGGCCAGCUACUUGGGAGAGUGAGGCAGGAGGAUCACUUGAGGCCAGGAUUUCAAAUCCAGCCUAGGUAACACUGAGACCUCCAUCUCGUAAAAGGCACAAAAACUAGUUAGAGAUGAAAUUGAGCUUUAUUUUAAAAAAACGUUCUAAAGCCUGAUAAUUGGAGAGCUAUACUUCAGCUUUUCAUCCUACUUUAAUGAAACAGCUAGAUAGGAACCUCUGCUCCAGAAUUGCCAGAUAAUUAUUGGUGGGUCAUAACUAUUCUUCAUAUUUUUUUUUUCUUUUUUCUCCUUUGGUUUCUGUGUUAUCUUUCUUAACCUCACGUAUUUCUUUAUCCUUUUUAGUGGGGGCCUGUAAUUGAGGCUAAUUCAAUAGCAACAAUAGACAACAUGAUAUGGCUGCUGUCACUUUGAAACCCAAAAGGUCUUUGGGUAGGAAUAGAGUAAUGAAAGAGGACCAGUCAACUUCAGUAUAUAUACAAAGGAAAGACAAAGAGAUGAUAAACCAAGGCUGAGGAAAUUUUUCUGAUGCUUUCUUCAUUUCUCUAAUAUACCUUUUGCAUUCUUUUUCUGAUAAUUGUGCUAUUAGGCAGAAGACACAAGUUACCACGUUGUGUAUUAAAAGCAGUAGGUAGGUUGUGCCAGUAUUUUUUCAGCCAGUAAGCAUAUACAGUUAACUUAUAUAAUUAAAAAUUGGUUUAAGAUAGUGAUUAAAAAUACCUGAAUAUUAUGUUAAAAGUAUACAAUCAUUGUUUCUGUAAUGAUGAUGGGUAUUCUGCUUCUUGUUUUUCAUUGUAAUUACAGGGGAAGAUUGUUUUUGAAAAUGUAUAUUGCCAUGCUUUUGGGGUAAGCAGUAAUGUGAAAAGAAAAAAGCAUUAUGUUAUUGUAUGAAAUAUAAGUGUUCAGAUUUGUUUUGUCUGGGGUGUUGCCUAAGAAUACCCUAAAGCUAUGGCUGUUACUGCAUUGAAAUCUUUUUUUUUUUUAAUAGUAGCCAUAUGUUAUUAGUGGAGUACUUUAUAUUUGACAUUAAAGUGAAGAAGAAGAGUAGUACUUCACUUUUAGGUUUUUAGUAGUGAAAGAUAAAAUUGGAAAAAUAGGGAAAGAGCAUAGGGAGGAAUAGAAUGGAAGUCAAGUAAAUAAAAAACUACAACCUGACAGUUUUUUAAAUCACUUUGAAAAGUACAUUACUUUUAUCAAAGAGUUUCUAAUUAAGGCAAACUAUGCAUUAUGCCAAAUAUUAAGAACAUUUUAAAAAUGGAUUGUGAUACUGUUUAUUUCUUUAAUUAUAUAAUUUGCAAUUUUCUGUAUUAUAAGUGCUACCAGGAUUCUAGAUAGUUGAUCUUACAUAUUCAGAUAGUAUAGUUUACUCUUAUAAUUACCCGUUACGUUAUCUCUAAAAGUAGUUUGAUCUGUGCCUUUAACUUUUAGAAUUCAUCUUUUGACUUGUUUGCCACUGUAGAGUUUUCAGUUUUCUCUGUAGAUUCAGUGUGACAAAGAGGGAAUACAUAAUUUGUGACCAUUUAAGAUGCUGAUAUUUUCUGGAAAAGGAUAUAGAUAGUAGUAGUGACCCGCAGGAGCCUCACAAUAAUGUCUAAAGAUAUAAACUGAGUAGAUCCCUAAGUACUCUUCUCUAAAUUAUAAAAUGCAUUACCUAGGCUUUAAUAGUUAAAAGCUGGAAUUUAUUGAACCGCAUCUACUUGAUUUCAUAAUAUGCAUUGAUUUUAGUAUGUUGCUGUUCUGUUAUCUGUAAUCAACUAUAACAGAGUAAUAUAUUUGGUGUUCUGGACCAAAAUUCGUGCUACACAUAUGUCUGAUGGCCUUUACCUUUUCAAGAAAACAGUUGCAAUUUUGAGCAAAAUUUUCCUAGUUGUAAUAUUUUAAUAGUGUUAUGUAUUGGAAAAAAUUUAGAAAUACUCCUAAGAGUUUUCAAUUUCAAGCAGAAAUGCUUCUCUUCUAAAUAAAUACCACUUAAUUGAUAGACCUUUAGCAGUUCUUGUGCUAUCUAGGAUUUAUACAUUUUUGCUUUUCUGGAAAACUGCUUUGGCGCAUUAACCUUUCUACUGCAACAUUUUCUCUUCAGUAGAUAUAUGAGUAAACAUGAUGAGUUAAUGUUACACAGCAUACCCAGUUAGGUCUCUUAUUCUUAAAGCAUCUUUCUUUAGAAGUCUGCACAUAUUUUCAAAUGCAUCAUAUUAAAGGCACAAGUCAAGAGGAGGUGGAGUUGCCUACUUCAGUGGCCUUUAUUCCCACUAUACCAGUUCUCAGUCUUGAUUUUGAUACUUUCUGGCAACUGUAUCAUCUCUUCACUAUCACGUAUUUUAAGAAAAAGCUAAGGUGAUUUCUUUACAUUUGAACAUGUGUAGAUCAAUGAGAGAAUGGUGAGGGAUAGCAAGGAUAAAGUAUAAUGUUGAAAAGUAGAAAGAAGUGGUAUCUGCUAAACUCUAGCUUUAGUAGCAAGCUAUUUUAAGGAAAUCAUUGUAUGUGGUACUUCCUAGAAAUAUGAAAGUUCCUCAUUUUGUAUUUAAUUAUGUAAGAAAAUGUUCUAGGAAAAGAAUAAAAAACAUAUAUUGUCAAAGUGCCCUUUGGUAGUGCUCCCAAAUGGUAGUAACUAUUGGUCUCUAGUAUAUACUCCUCAAAUAUCUUUUUGCUAUGUAUUAAUAUAUCUAUAUGUUUACAUAUAGAAAUACAUAGUGUUGUGGGUUUUAAAUUUUCACAUAAAUUGUGUCUUACCCAUGUGUUUUGCCAUUUGCCUUUUCUCUUGCCAACGUGUCUAGGAGCUCUUUGGUAAAUACAGACUUUUUCAUUUUAUUUCCUCCCACAUUUCUAUGGAUGUGUCUUGCCUUUUUCUUUUUUUUUUCUUUCUUUUUUUCUUUUUUAAAAUAGCCUCUGACUCCAUGAAACCUGAAAAGGAAUCUGGUCUGUUAGGUGGAUUUCAUUAGUAUCCAAAUUUAUUUAUUUUUUUAUUUCAUUUUUUUGAGACAGUCUCGCUGUGUCACCCAGGCUGGAGUGUGGUGGCUCAGUGAUAGUUCACUGCAUCCUUGAACUCAUGGACUCAAGCAAUCCUCUUGCCUCAGCCUUCUGAGUAGCUGGGACUACAUGUGUAAGCCACCAUGCCUGGCUAAUUUUUGUAUUUUUCAUUUUUAGUAGAGAUGGGAAGUCUUGCUGUGUUGCCCAGGCUGGUCUUGAACUCCUGGCCUCAACCAUUCCUCCCACUUCAGCCUCCCAAAGUACUGAGAUUACAGAUGUGAGCCACUAGGCCCAGUCAGUAUCAUAGAAUUUAAAUGCAAGCCAAUGCUUAGACAGAAUCAGGGUCUGCUUUAAGCAUGUGAAUCAGGAAACUAGAAGGCCUCUUGUAAUGUAUUUGAAGUUCAUUACUUUUGGCUGACGGUUGACUGCUUAGUGUAUAAAAUCUAGGAGUUAACUUUAGCAGAUUCUUUUAUCAGAAUACGUUUUUUAUUGGAGGGAAGAAGGAAAAAGAGGAAAGGUAUAACUGAUGGGGAAAAGUACAAGAUAAACUAAAACAAGUCUUUAUACAACUCUGACAGCAACUCCCAUAACAGGACAUGAUGCUACCAAAAAUUCAAACUUGUAUUUGAUCUGUGCCUUUAAUAUAGAGUAAAAACAAAAGUUCCUUUUUAGAUCUCCCUUCCCUCAUCAUCCCACAUCCCUUUUUAGAGGUAACCAUUGUUAACAGUUUGGUUUGUGUCUUUAUUAUGCAGUUUUAUAUUUAUAUUUGGCCUUUGUAAAUUUUCCAUUCCCUGAAUGGAACUUCUACCCUAUAUCAAAUUCCACCCUCAACUGACCAAUUUACCAAGGCCAACUAGAAUCAUACUUCUUUUUCUGGAAGUUUUUUUUGAGACAGGGUCUUGCUUUGCCGCACAGACUAGAAUGCAGUAGCAUGAUCAUAGCUCAUUGCAGCCUCAAACUCCUGGGCUUAAGCAAUCCUCCCACCUCAGACUUCGAAGUAGCUGGUAUUACAGGUGCAUAACACCACCACCCACGCCUGGCUAAUUGUUUUGUUUUUUUUGUGGAGAUGGCUCUCACUUUGUUGCCCAGGCUGGUUUUUGAACUAGUUUCAAAGUGAUCCUCCUGCCUUGGCCUCUCAAAGUACUAGGAUAACAGUCAUGAGCCACCAUGCCCACCCUAGAAUCAUACUCUUUUAAAGCAAGUUAAAUCAGCAGUAAUAGUUCUGGAACUAGAAGUUAACUACUUACUGGACUUUUGAGAUGUAAGUUUACCAUACAUCAAGCUUAAAAACUUGUAGCGUUCUGGGAAAGUCAAGUCAAACUCUUGAAUGCUAUCCUCUGUGGAAAUAGGGUUGGGAAAGAGCAAUGUACAAGUCCAAGCUCCUUAAUACACAUAAAACUCUGGGUUGGGCUCAUCCUCUUGGUGUAUUUUCCUACUUGGAGAGCAUUACAGUGUCCAACAAUUUAUAGGAGCUUCUCUGCACUGUCAAGACUAUAGCUUAGCAUAUGUGUGCUAUGACACAAGGUUAAACGUGUGCCCCAGAACAAAUGCAUUUAUUCAUGUUUGACUUUAAAUGAAAAUUCAGAAAGCAGGUUAAGCAUAUAUGUGAGUUUAAUAAUUGUUUCUGUAUUUUAAAAAAUUUUAAAACAUUCAGCUUUUUAUGACUUUGGUUAGUUUCACUCAUUUGUUGAGUGCCUUCUGUAUGCCCAGUGCACAAACUGCUAUGUGCCCAGUGUACAUACAUGGGAGAACCAGAUAGCCAAAGUGCCUUCCUUUAUCGUUGGAACCUAGAGAUGAGCUGAUACCUGUUGCACAUAGUCCAAGAUAUAAGUAAUUUAUCUGGGGAUAUAAGGUCACCUGUGCACACAUGUUCACAUUCUGUGUUUGAUCAGAUAUGUACCUGCCAAACUUUUGGAGUGAGAUAAUUAGAAUGACAGUAGUUGAAGCUGACAGUGAAUUUGAGGUAAAGCUGGAAAGAAUGUUUUUGAAUUUUGCAAAUAAUACAUUUUCAAGCCAGAUUAAAAUUGAAUAACUUACUUUCUAGCUUCAAGGGGGUAAUUAAGUGAUCCUCUAACCCAAAUUGCUUUUCCAAAUUUUGUGGUAGCAGUGAAUAAACUGAUGCCUCCUGCUUAUUUAGACAGCAGCCAUUUUUGUUUGGUUUGGUUUGGUUUUGCGGUGAUUUUUUUUAACCUAGAAAAAAUACAAUUUAAAAAGCAAUCAUGUUGUUUUCUUUGCCUUUGACAGAUGUGGCCUUGUCACCACACAGUAAGCCAGAACACAAUCCAUUCCUGAGUCAUAGUAGGAUAGUUUGUGUAAUUCUAAAUGCACUCUCCAGUUUAAGAGUGUGGGUCCCUUUUUUUCUAUCUGAAAUUGAAGAUACAGGUCAGAAAGAUGGUUUAAUGAAUAUGAAUUUUCUAAACAUCUUUUCAGUGUCUUUUAAGGAUAUUUUUGAUAUUACAAUAUAAUAAAGUUAAAUCAUCUAGUCCUCCUGGCCCUUCUGGUUAGAAAAUAGAGCGAAAUCAUCCGUUUAAACACACACACACAAACUAUCCCAUUAGUUGGUUAUACACAAGUUACUUUCAUUCUUACUAGUUCACAAAAGGUUAGUAAAUUUAGUGAUUUAAUGAGUUCUUCAAAACAUAAAAGUCCUGUAAAGGAAAAGCUAGAGGAUGUGAGAGGAGUAAUUCAUCCCCAUCAAAAGAUUUUAGCCAAAAGUAGUGGCAUAAGAAAUUUAUUUAUGCGAAAGACAUAAUUUUGGGUGAACUUUCUUGAAGAUGGUCAGAAAGGGCAUUGUUAAAGGAAGGAGAUGGUAGAUUUUGGGUUCUGGGUUCUAGGUUCUAGGCUAAUAAUUUACUACUUUGGUAUGUUGCCUUGAGGCUGACAUUUGCUGCUCUGCUAAGACUAAAGCUGGCCCUUUCCAAUCAAAAGUGUUAAAAGCUGGCUGGGAGCCAUGGCUCAUGCCUGUAAUCCAGCACUUUGGGAGGCUGAGGUGGGUGGAUGGAUCCCUUAAACCCAGGAAUUCAAGACCAGUGUAGACAACAUGGCGAAACCCCAUCUCUAUCCAAAAAUAUACAAAAAUUAGCCAGGUGUGGUGGUGUGUGCCUGUAGUCUCAGCUACUCAGGAGGCUGAGAUGGGAGGAUUGCUUGAGCCUGGGAGUUAGAGGAUGCAAUGAGCUGAGGUCGCACCACUGCACUCCAGCCUGGACGACAGAGUGAGGCCCUGUCUCAAAAAAAGAAAAAAGAAAAAAAAAAGUUAAAAGUUGUGGCAUGGUGGCUCACGCCUGUAAUCCCAGCACUUUUGGAGGCUAAGGCAGGUGGACCACCUGAGGUCAGGAGUUCGAGACCAGCCUGGCCAACAUGGUGAAACCCUGUCUCUACUAAAAACAAAACAAAACAAAACCAUAUAUAUAUUAUAUAUAUAUAUAUAUAUAUAUUUUUUUUUUUUUUUUUUUUUUUUUUUUUGAGACGGAGUCUCGCUCUGUCCCAGGCCAGAGUGCAGUGGCGCUAUCUCGGCUCACUGCAAGCUCCGGCUCCCGAGUUCACACCAUUCUCCUGCCUCAGCCUCCCGAGUAGCUGGGACUACAGGCGCCCGCCACCACGCCUGGCUAAUUUUUUGUAUUUUUUUGGUAGAGAUGGGGUUUCACCGUGUUAGCCAGGAUGGUCUCUAUCUCCUGACCUUGUUAUCCGCCCGCCUCGGCCUCCCAAAGUGCUGGGAUUACAAGCGUGAGCCACCGAGCCCAGCUAUAUUUAUAAAUUUAUAUAUAUUUCAUAUAUAUAUUAUAUAUAUAUAAAAUUAACCGGGCAUGGUAGUGAGCCCCUGUAAUCCCAGCUACUUGGGAGGCUGAGGCAGGAGAAUUGCUUGAACCCAGGAGACGGAGGUUGCAGUGAGCAGACCUGGUGCCACUGGACUCCAGCCUCGGUGACAGAGUGAGACUCUGUCUCAAAAAAAAAGUUAAAAGUUGUUAACUAGAUGUCGAAUUAUUUUCAUAGUAAUCACCAUGUGUAAGCAAUUCUCAUCUGUGGAAUGUUUGACAGGGAUAAGAUUAUUGAAAAUUGGGGGGAAUUUUCUUAAAUAUGGAACUAAGAGCUAAAGAGUUCAAUGAUGAUUAAGACCACUAGUCUGGCAAGUGACUUUUAUUUGUCCUUUUCUAUUGAUAAUGAAUUCUAGGAAUAUGGAUGGAUUUCAUUAGAGAAAUAAAAAUGAGCAAGAUUUGUGAUUCAGAAUAUUAAAAGUUAAGAAUCCAUGAAUAGCCCCUUAAAAAUAUUGUCAAAGCAUCAUGGUAUUUGUAGUGGUGCUUAAAAAAGAAGCAGCAGCAGCUGUUCUAAGCCAAGCACUGCUUGAAAACAAAACAAAACAGAACAAAACCUUAUAUUUAAUAAAAUGGAGAAAUUUGGGAAUGUCCCUAGCGUAAUAAUGCCUUCUACUGACAUUUAAAGUCAGCUUAAACAUCAUUAGGGAAGACUAUGACUGUUUCUAUGACCUCUAGUCACAAAUUUAACUAAUUUAAGGUUAACUAAUACCUCUUUCAGAGUUGGGCAAAAGAAGAAAAAAAAAGCCUUUAUUUGUGAUCAGUAAAUUAUAAAUUACACAGAAGCUUCCAGCUACCUGGUAUUUGCAUGAAGAAUUCUAAAUUUUUUAUAUGCCAUAAUUUUUAGUAAUGCUGUCCUUGAAUUCACUUACAUCUCUGCUCUGGUUUUUUGAAGCUCAUUAGGAUGAUACCUGUCAUCUCUUGGAAACACUGGAACUAGAGAACUGGAGGUGUUCACCCCCAUUUUUUGCUACAUUGUUGAAAACUGAGUAGAAUUUUGUGUCCAAAAAUCCUUAGUCUGUGAUGGAAUUUUUUAAAGUAUAUGUGAAGUUUUUUACUUCUUCAGUUUUUCAAGAUAAUUUUGCUGUUUUUGCUUUUUAUUUAUUUGCAACUAGAAAUUGCAUGUGCCAGUUACUUAAUUUAAUACAUCUAAUGGGAGAUUCAAAGCAAACCAUUAAAACUACCAUAUAAACUCAAAUGAAAUUUUAUGACAUUCUAAUGUACAUACUCGCCAAGAAAUGCUACAAGGAGCCUCUCUGCAAAUGCCUGAUGGGGCACUCUGAGAAUUAAACAGGAAAUGGACAGGAAAAGAGGCAAAGCAUAGAAUAGCCUCUGUGGUAUACACACAGACAAUGUAAAAUCCAAGAAAUAUAAGGUCCAAGGAGGAAUUGGUUAUUGAAGUAGAGAACCUCAUCAUGAGAUUUGAGAAUAGCUUUAGAGUUACUCUUGGGAUAGUGUCUCAUGGCCCUGUGAGGGAACUCUACAAAUUUUAUCCAUUUUGCUGGGCAGUUUUAAGAGCUACUUUUUGUCUGUACUUUCCUUAAUUUUCAUAUUAUUUCUAGCUUUUACUUCAUCUUAUGAAAGAUUAACUUAGAGGUUAGAAUGCUUACAUUUGCAAAUAGCCUGAGGAAUAAAUAUGUGCUUUAUCAAAGUGGAACUUCUGAUUUUCUGUAAUAUUAGGAUGGACAUGUGUCUGGCUUAUCCUUCCUAUCUAGGAAACUGGUGUCAUUAGGAAAUACGUUAACAUAAGAUCCCUGACUAUAAAGUAAGACUUAUUAUCUUGUAUAGUUUGUAGCAUUUAAUCUUCUAUUUCAGUGAUUGGUUUGGAUCUACUUAAUUUUAAGCUUUACUGGUCAUUUGUCCCCCUCAUGUUGUACCUAAUAAGUGUGUAGUUUUUAAGUGAAAUCAUACAUAAUUUCAAGGAAACUGCUAGAGACAAUGUUGAGUAUCAUCAAGAACAUUUAAUCAAACCUGUUGACUAAGAGCUUUAGUUUGGCUUACAAUUUCAUAUGUAAAUCCAAGAAAAAGACUUGUAAGCUAAAAAGCCUGUUUCGUUCGGAAAAAAAAGUACAUAACAUUUUAAAGAUUUGUGAGAGGAAAAAAGCAUUAGAUGCGAUAGAAUGGAAUAAUCUCUUUUUAGAAGUAAAUUAGUUUUUAUUUCAUUUGUGGGUGGUAUUGAGAAAAGUGGUGGAAAUAAAUACAUUGAGCAGAUUCAGAAUUUAAUAGACACUUCGUGUUUCCAUUUUCAUAAUGGGGGUUAGUCAUAAACCAUUCUAUGUGGAGCAUUUUACAGGGGCUCUGAAAGGUAUACAAAAUGUACUACUAUAAUUAAUGUCCUCAAGGAACUUAAAAACCUAUUGGAAGAUUUAUUUAACAGAGGUAAGAGAAUUUGGACCCAUUAAAAAUGGAGGAAAAGGUAAAGUUAGUAUUUGUAGAUGAUAGUGCAAAGCUUAAAAGGGUCAACUGAAAGUCUCUUAAAACGAAUACAGUCACUGGGUAUAAAAUUCAUCACAGAAAUAAAAAGCUUUCAUUUAUAAAAACAACAGCCAGUUAGAAGAUAUAAUAGAAGAAAAGGCCCCAUUUAAAGUAAGACCAAAGGAGAGAAGAUACCUAGGAAUAAACAAGUUAUAUGCGUGACCACAAAACCAAAACUUUGUAUUUCACAUGAAAAUAAAUUCAAACACAUGGAGAUGCAUAUCAUAUUCUUGGAUAGGAAGACAACAUACACAUUUCAGUUCUCUAAAUUGAAUGCAAUCCCAAUAAAAAUAUAAGGAUUAAAAAAAAAAAAAACUAGAUCGCUGAUUCCAAAGUUUCUUUGAGGAAAAAAAAAAAAAAAAGCAAGACUAGCCAGGAAAACUGAAAAAACAAUGAGGAAAGACUGGCCUUAUGAAAUAUUUAAACAAGAGAGCUCCAAUAAUUAAAACAGUCUGGAACUGGCAUAUGACUAGACAGAUCAUUCAAGCAGAAGGAAAAUGAACCCAGAUAUGGGAAUUUAGUGGAGGAGAAGUGAUGUUUCAGCUCAGUGGGGAAAAUAUGGUUUAUUCAUUAAAGGUAGUAGGACACUUGGGUAGCUAUAGAGAACAAAGCUGGAUUCAUACCUCAUAAACCAAAAUGCAUUCCAGUUUAAAUAUGAAAACUGAAAUGUUUAAAGUACCCAAAGAGGUUGUCAGAGAAUUUUUAAAGAUUUUAGUGUGGUAAAGGAUUUCCUGAAUUUGAUAUAAAAUUUGGAAUAGAAUUUACAAUAAGAAAUGAUAAUGUUUUCACUAUAAAUUUGUAACAAUAAAUUAUUAUUAUUUUUGAGAUGGAGUCUCACUCUAUUGCCCAGGCUAGAGGGCAGCGGCAUGAUCUUGGCUCACUGCAACCUCUGCCUCCCAGGUUCAAGCAAUUAUUCCUACCUUAGCCUCCCAAGUAGCUGGGACUACAGGUGUGCACCACCACACCUGGCUAAUUUUUGUAUUUUUAGUAGAGAUGGCGUUUCACAGUGUUGGCCAGUCUGGUCUUGAAUUCCUGACCUCAAGUGAUCUGCCCACCUCGACCUGCCAAAGUGCUGGGAUUAUAGGUGUGAGGCACCAUGCCCAACAUAUAACAAUAAAUUAUAUCACUAUAUAAAAUAAAUUCCUCACAGCAAAAAACCACCAUAAGCAUAGUCUAAAGAAAAAUGACAAAUUUGGAAAAAAUAUUUUCAAAUCAUAUCAUGCAUUGCUUAAUUUAUAAAGAACACCUAGAAAUGAAAAAGUCCAAUGAUCCAAAAAGAAAAAGGUACAAAAUUGUAAACAGUUUUCACAGAAAAGAAUAAAAUGAUUCAAGCCGGAAAAAAAGUUCAACUUUAUUACUAAGAGAAGUAUAAGACAAAACUAUACUGAGAUACCAGUUUUUUAACCUAUUAAUCAAGAAAGACUUUUUAGUUUUAUAAAACAUUGUAAUAUUCUAGAUAUUAUUGGUAAGAAUGGAGGGAACAAGUAUUUUUGCUGAUAGAGGGGUAAACUGGAACAACCGCUAAGGAUGACAGUGAAUUCUGAAUUUAUUUACCCAAUGUACUCUUCAAGUUGCAGAGGCUGAGAAAUUAUUAAACUGUUACCCAGAACUUUUUAUGCAGAUGGGGGGGCAGUCUGAAUGCUAAUUAAGUUUUCUCAACUAUAUGCUCUCUCCUCAUGAUUUGAAAGGCAAAAGUGAAGCAGAGGCCAAGUUUUGAAGUUCUUGAAUGUUACGAGGUAGUGAAAAACGUUUCCAUGCAGCAGUGAUCAAGUGUCUAUCGUUCAGCUUCCUGAAUAUGGAUAGGCUGUGGUGGUGGCAGCAGCUUCUUAAUCUGACAUUCCAACCCCUAGAUUGUGGUGUUACAUCUUCUUUCUCCAGCUUCCCAGGAGUGAAAGGUUGUAGUGGCUGGCCUCUGGUUCCCAGCAGGGCUCCAUGGUGACCAGAGGUUGUAGUUCCCCCAGUGAAUCAUGUUUGUGUCACUGUGGGAUUCAUUCCCAUAGGCUCAACUUAGAUUCCUAAACCCUGCUCCUUCAACCCUUCCAGUAACUUUAUAAGCACCAAAUUCCAUUUAAAAAGUGCCUUCCUGUUUAAAAUAUCUAUAAUGGCUUCUGUUUCCUGCAUUGAAAGCUGACUGAUCUGGAGGGCAAUUGGGCAACAGCAAUCAAAAUUGUCUUUUCUUUUGACCUAGCAGUUUCACUUCUUGGAAUAUAUCCUGUAAAUAUGCUUAUGUAUGAAGGAAAUGAGUUUGUACAACGUUUUUCAAUGCAGUAUUGUUUGUAAAUUGACACCAGUAGGGGAAUAGUAAAAUCAAUUACUAUGCAUGCAUAUAAUAAAAUUUUAGGUAGCUAUAAAAAAGAGAAUGAGAAAGCUUUGCAUAUUUAAAAGAAACCAUCAACAGGAAUAUUAAGUUUUUAAAAAAAGCCAGGGCAGAACAGUCUGUAUACUGUAUAUUUUAAAAUUGAACAAGUAUAGUAGACAAUUGAAGUAUAGUAAAGAUAAAAUUAAUUGCACAGGCCAGGCACAGUGGUUCACACCUGUAAUCCCAGCAUUUUGGGAGGCCAAGAUGGGCGGAUCAUAUGAGGUCAGGAGUUCAGGACCAGCCUGGCAAAUACGGUGAAAUCCCAUCUCUACUAAAAAUACAAAAAUUAGCCGGGUGUGGUGGCAAGCAACUAUAAUCCUAACUACUUGGGAGGCUGAGGCAGGAGAAUUGCUUGAACCCGGGAGGCGGAGGUUGCAGUGAGCCAAGAUCAUGCCCCUGUACUCCAGCCUGAGCAACAGAGUGAGACUCUAUCUCAAAAAAAAAAAAAAAAAAAUUAAUUGCACAUGAAGUAUACAAGUUCGAUCUGUGAAACCACCAUCACAGUGAAGAUAAUUAACACAUCCAUCAUUCCACAAAAUUUCCUUACACUUUCUUGUAAUCCCUUCUCCCUCCCAUUCCUGCUUUCUUUAAACUAUAGUUUAGUUUGAAUUUUCUAUAAUUUUAUAUAAAUAAAAUCAUAUAACAUGUA